GGUCUGCGGUCGGGCUGAGACACGCGGAGCAAUGGCGACCUUUGUGAGCGAGCUGGAGGCGGCCAAGAAGAACUUAAGCGAGGCCCUGGGGGACAACGUGAAACAAUACUGGGCUAACCUAAAGCUGUGGUUCAAGCAGAAGAUCAGCAAAGAGGAGUUUGACCUUGAAGCUCAUAGACUUCUCACACAGGAUAAUGUCCAUUCUCACAAUGAUUUCCUCCUGGCCAUUCUCACGCGUUGUCAGAUUUUGGUUUCUACACCAGAUGGUGCUGGAUCUUUGCCUUGGCCAGGGGGUUCCGCAGCAAAACCUGGAAAACCCAAGGGAAAGAAAAAGCUUUCUUCUGUUCGUCAGAAAUUUGAUCAUAGAUUCCAGCCUCAAAAUCCUCUCUCAGGAGCCCAGCAAUUUGUGGCAAAGGAUCCCCAAGAUGAUGACGACUUGAAACUUUGUUCCCACACAAUGAUGCUUCCCACUCGAGGCCAGCUUGAAGGGAGAAUGAUAGUGACUGCUUAUGAGCAUGGGCUGGACAAUGUCACCGAGGAGGCUGUUUCAGCUGUUGUCUAUGCUGUGGAGAAUCACCUUAAAGAUAUACUGACGUCAGUUGUGUCAAGAAGGAAAGCUUAUCGGUUACGAGAUGGUCAUUUUAAAUAUGCCUUUGGCAGUAACGUGACCCCGCAGCCAUACCUGAAGAAUAGUGUAGUAGCUUACAACAACUUAAUAGAAAGCCCUCCAGCUUUUACUGCUCCCUGUGCUGGUCAGAAUCCAGCUUCUCACCCACCCCCUGAUGAUGCUGAGCAGCAGGCUGCACUCCUGCUGGCAUGCUCCGGAGACACUCUACCUGCAUCUUUGCCUCCGGUGAACAUGUACGAUCUUUUUGAAGCUUUGCAGGUGCACAGGGAAGUCAUCCCUACACAUACUGUCUAUGCUCUUAACAUUGAAAGGAUCAUCACGAAACUCUGGCAUCCAAAUCAUGAAGAGCUGCAGCAAGACAAAGUUCACCGCCAGCGCUUGGCAGCCAAGGAGGGGCUUUUGCUGUGCUAAAUUAGGAUUUGAGGGUGUGGGACCCUCACCGAAUUCAUUGAUUACUGAAAAUUGAAUGUUUUUUGGGUCCACAUUUCAAGGCUGAAGUGUAUAGUGUAUAUAUAACCUUUCCUAUGGAAAUGUGACAUUGAGUACAUUUUGUGUUGCUGUUGUGAAGCCAUUAAUAUAAAUCUUUGGUAAUGACCCAUAUCUCUAUAUGUAUGUGUUCCCAGUUGUGGGAGCAGGCACUAAUGAAAUCCUGUGCCUGGAAUGGAGAUAUUUAGGUACCUGAGGCUUAGUGUCCUGUGGUCUGCAUGUAAGAUAGAUGACAUCCUAGAACAAAGAAGCUGUUUUAACUUAAUCCCCCUGAUCAGCAGGAUAUCUGUGUGUUCAGUGACAUCAUACAUUCUGUAUCUAGAAGUCUAAAAUUUCUGCCUUUCUCCUAAAGAAUGUGUUCUUGCAUUUUGGUUGAAAUAACCUACACAGUGUUAAAAAUCAGAUACCUCCUUUAGUGACCAGUUCAAAUUUUAAUAGCGAUAGGUAGCCCCUGAGAAAUUUAUCACUAUAACUCCACAGGAAAUAUGACUUGGAAGUGCUCUGUGUACUAAACAAAAUAAAGCCCCUCUUUGCAUUUAAAACCAAAGUCAAAACAAAACUCUUGUAAUGCAAUUAAUUAACUUUAUGUCUUCCCAUGACUCAAGUUUUGUUAAAUAUGCCCAAAAACUUUGAUUGGCAGUUUCUUCGGUUAAUUAUUCCUAUAGAAUGUAUUUUAAGAAAUCUAUACAAAUUGGAUAUAUGCUUGGUAAUUCUCCAGUUUCUAGGAGGUACCUAUUUCUACCGUUUCAAGUGAUGAAGUGAAAAUAAUUUACAUUCGAUAGUGUUACUGAUAACAAACCUACUUAAGAGAUAUGUUGCUUUUUACUUAAGGGAUAGUGUUGAUAGAUAAAUUAGAAUGUAUAGAUAGGUUUGUGAAAGUCUAAAUAAUGGUUGUAUAGAUAUGUAUAUAUGGUUCACAUAUCUGGAUCUGUGUAUUUGAUUUUGUACUUUAAAUGUGACAAAUAAACCUUUUGGGAGAAAA